ACUGAGGUAUUCCUUCCCCUCUCAGGACUAGCCACAUGCUGUCUCUCUGCCCUGGCCUCUUCCACCCCAUGCCCAGUCAGAGACCGUUUUGAGGGUAGAGAAGCCAGUCUACGGCCCACCACGGGAGCCACCGCCUGGGCCAGACAUGAAGCGCUGGCAGAUUUUUGUCCUGUGGGUCUUUUGGGUGCUCAUCCUCUGGCUGAUGACCCCCUAUCUGGAUCUGACACCUGAAUCAGCACCCCAGGAAAAACGAAUGUACUUGGUACCACAGCAUUGCGACUGCCCUUGGUUCAGUUCCGGGAAGUGUGGCUGCCCUUCUGAGACCCUCAACUGCUCCUCCUGCCACCACACAGCCGACGAAUGGAACUGGCUUGAUGCGUGCUCCAGGAAGACUAUGGGGUACCUGAUGAGGACAAGAGAGUCUAUGACCUCUGACACUGUGCUCUGGUGGUUGGGCAUGAACUCAGGGAGCGAGCUUGGGAAAUUGUGGAGGAAGCUGUUUAAAGGGAUUCCCAGGCUCUCGGUGAGCCAUUUUGAUUUCUAUUGUGGGACUUGUGUGCUGUUGGGGCGCCCACAGAUCCCGCAGGGCUCCAGCCUUGGCAACGACAUCGACCAAUACCCCGUGGUUUUCAGGAAUGCCAGCGACCAGGGCUCCUGGAUGCAGCUGGAGAUGCUACUGCGGAAGCUCUCUGACCUGGUGUGGACUUCAGAUGCUCUAAGUGAUAAGAUUUUGGAAGAUGGUCUGGUUCCCUAGUGGAGUGGAAGAUAGCAAAGACACGGUCACCCUCUUUGGAUUUGGAUCAGAAUAGCAAGGAAAGUGUUUCUAUCACUGGAAGGAGGAUAAUCAGACCAAGGGCUCCAAGGAAAUACUGCCCACGUCUAGUGCAGGAGCAGAAAUCGAAGUCAUCCAUCAGCUAGCGUGUGGACAAGCUCACUAUUCACACAAGCUCAGCCUAGCUGAGUCCAUACAAAUCCUAUUUCUGGCACUCCAGCCAGAAGGACCUCCGUAAUAUGGCCAAGAUACACCCAGGAAUCUGCCACCAUCCCAGCAACUUUUCCAGAAAAUGCAACUGCUCAUCUGAGGUCCACACAUGCUCUGCCUGCCUCCACGUGCCUGGCGAGUCUGACUGGUUUGACAGACGCUUCGACAGUACCGUUGAACCCCUACAGAGGCCACAAGAUCCCACGUCCAAUGAUGCUCUGAUAUUGUGGCUGGGACUCGAGAGGGUCAAGUCAGAGAAGGAGGUUGAGAAUAAGCAGCAGCAGCUGAUUAAAGCACCUCCCCUGUGCCCACUGGGCCAUGUGGUGUCCAACUGCCGGGUCUGUGCAGUGGUGGGAAACUCAAGGUCUCUAUGGAGCUCUGGCCUUGGCUUCAGGAUUAAUCAACAUGAAGUGGUCCUCAGGAUGAACCAGGCCCCUGUCUGAGGCUUUGAGGCAGAUGUGGGGAACAGGACCACCAUGCGCGUUAUGUACCCUGGGAUUGCCAGCCCUCAGGACCCCGGUACCCAACUGCUGCUGCUUCCGUUGAAUUCAUCUGGUCUGGAGUGGUUCAUAAGUGUACUGCAUAAACAGACAAGCAUGUGGAAGCAAAAAAAACCCUGGAUUUCAGACGGUUCAGGUUCCUGGUGGAACCGAAGACAGCAAAGAUAAGGUGCUGGUGAUCAGCCUCUACUUCCUCAGGUAUAUCCAGGAAAGUUGGCUGGAGAACCAUGGUCAGUAUCCGUCCUUGGAGUUUGUGGCUCUGUUGUAUGCCUUGCAUACCUGUGACCAGAUUCCCGCACUGGACUUCUUGGGGUUCUCCAAACAUACCAGCUGCCUCACGCCUUCUCACACCUUGCUCCCUCUGCCUGGAAUGCCCUUCCCUUGUCUCCCAGGGGAAUCCUCUCUUCUCUCAAUAUAUAAUGAAGAACAACUAGUUGGUGCUCUCUUUUCUGGGCUCUGGGGUCACUAUGAGUAUUUAGAGUCUGUCUUCCUUGAAGAAGGUGAACUCCAUUCUCCUCCCAGCUCCAAGAGGAAGCCUGGCACACUAGUGGUUGAGUGAGUGGUGCUGAAGGCAUGAUAGGUGUUCCAUGGGGGCAGGGCAGGAUCCAGCCCGUUACACCACCACCAUCUUUUGUCUUAUCCAAUCUCUCAGGUAUCCUUGUUUGGUUUUGGGGAAGACAAUUGCAAAAGGUGGUCCCAUUACUGGGAUGACAAAUAUUGGUUUGAGAACACCAUGCAAAAUUUCCCAGCAGAAUACCAGAUCAUCUUGAAACUGCAGUGUGAGAGGAAGAUUGCUGUCUACGGCUGAGAUGUUUCCAGUGGAGUCCCCAGGAGGCUUGACAGGUAGCCAAGGGGACCUUGUGGUGUCAGAGAGGGACUAGGGCUUCAAGCAGACCCUGGAUGGAGAUUACUCUGCUACUGAAUAAAACCCUAGCUUAUUUCUCUCUCUGGAUUUCUGGUGGCAUUAAAGGGCUACAUUCUAUUACUGA